AAGCACUUCCUUUUCCUGUGGCAGCAGCCGGGCUGAGAGGAGCGUGGCUGUCUCCUCUCUCCGCCAUGGCGUGUGCUCGCCCACUGAUAUCGGUGUACUCCGAAAAGGGGGAGUCAUCUGGCAAAAAUGUCACUUUGCCUGCUGUAUUCAAGGCUCCUAUUCGACCAGAUAUUGUGAACUUUGUUCACACCAACUUGCGCAAAAACAACAGACAGCCCUAUGCUGUCAGUGAAUUAGCAGGUCAUCAGACUAGUGCUGAGUCUUGGGGUACUGGCAGAGCUGUGGCUCGAAUUCCCAGAGUUCGAGGUGGUGGGACUCACCGCUCUGGCCAGGGUGCUUUUGGAAACAUGUGUCGUGGAGGCCGAAUGUUUGCACCAACCAAAACCUGGCGCCGUUGGCAUCGUAGAGUGAACACAACCCAAAAACGAUACGCCAUCUGUUCUGCCCUGGCUGCCUCAGCCCUACCAGCACUGGUCAUGUCUAAAGGUCAUCGUAUUGAGGAAGUUCCUGAACUUCCUUUGGUAGUUGAAGAUAAAGUUGAAGGCUACAAGAAGACCAAGGAAGCUGUUUUGCUCCUUAAGAAACUUAAAGCCUGGAAUGAUAUCAAAAAGGUCUAUGCCUCUCAGCGAAUGAGAGCUGGCAAAGGCAAAAUGAGAAACCGUCGCCGUAUCCAGCGCAGGGGCCCGUGCAUCAUCUAUAAUGAGGAUAAUGGUAUCAUCAAGGCCUUCAGAAACAUCCCUGGAAUUACUCUGCUUAAUGUAAGCAAGCUGAACAUUUUGAAGCUUGCUCCUGGUGGGCAUGUGGGACGUUUCUGCAUUUGGACUGAAAGUGCUUUCCGGAAGUUAGAUGAAUUGUACGGCACUUGGCGUAAAGCCGCUUCCCUCAAGAGUAACUACAAUCUUCCCAUGCACAAGAUGAUUAAUACAGAUCUUAGCAGAAUCUUGAAAAGCCCAGAGAUCCAAAGAGCCCUUCGAGCACCACGCAAGAAGAUCCAUCGCAGAGUCCUAAAGAAGAACCCACUGAAAAACUUGAGAAUCAUGUUGAAGCUAAACCCAUAUGCAAAGACCAUGCGCCGGAACACCAUUCUUCGCCAGGCCAGGAAUCACAAGCUCCGGGUGGAUAAGGCAGCUGCUGCAGCAGCGGCACUACAAGCCAAAUCAGAUGAGAAGGCGGCGGUUGCAGGCAAGAAGCCUGUGGUAGGUAAGAAAGGAAAGAAGGCUGCUGUUGGUGUUAAGAAGCAGAAGAAGCCUCUGGUGGGAAAAAAGGCAGCAGCUACCAAGAAACCAGCCCCUGAAAAGAAGCCUGCAGAGAAGAAACCUACUACAGAGGAGAAGAAGCCUGCUGCAUAAACUCUUAAAUUUGAUUAUUCCAUAAAGGUCAAAUCAUUUUGGACAGCUUCUUUUGAAUAAAGACCUGAUUAUACAGGCAGUGAGAAACAUGACUUGGUGUGCUCUGUAAAGCUUGGUUAGAAUUUUUUUAAAGUGACAUUUUGUUGGCCAUAAUUUAGACUGUUACAUUUUAUAUAGUGUGGUAUAAAAUGGGGCAUGGAUUUAUACUAAGUCCAUGGAGUUCAGUGGAAGGGGAAUGAUUUAAAAAAAGUUGUGGUUUUCUAAAUAAUGUGGCUUGAAAAAUAGGUGUAACAGGACUUGGUCAGAAACGCAGAGGCUGUUCAAGUUUAGCUCCCCACCAGAUGGAAAAUAGGUUAAAUUCUGUAAAGAUUUAACUUUAACCACAAGAGGGCACAACUGGAGAGCACAAUUUUUUUGGUACUGCAGUAAAAUUGAUUACCUCUUGAGAAGUGUUCUUUUUAACCAGCUAUAACAAUAGAGUUGAGUAUUUUCACCCAUGGUUUGAAAAAGUGCCAGAAGGCCACACUGGCCCACAUCUGUAAUCCCAACACUUUGGGACCCUAAGGUGGGCAGAGCACUUGAGCCAAUGAGUUCAAGACCAGCCUGGUCAACAUGAUGAAAUCUCGUCUCUACUGAAAAUAUAAAAAAUAGCCAGUCAUGGUGCAUGCCUGUAACCCCAGCUACUUGGAGGCUGAGGCAAGAGAAUCACUUGAACCUGGGAGGUGGAGGUUGCAAUGAGCCAAGAUUGUACCAUUGCCCUCCAGCCUGGGCGUCAGAGCAAGACUCUCUGAAAAGUACCAGAAGCAUUUUUCAGGACUGCCUGUGUGUCUUGGUGAUUAUGUUAACCAACUGUGUUCAAAAGAAGUACCCAUGAAAUGCCUCCAGAUAUAAGGGUGUUUUUUUUUACCCAUAAAGCUAAACUGCAAAUAUUACCCUAGAAUUAACCUCUUGUCCUGUGUCAAAAGUCUUGUUUUGCAUCUGGAUUGUUAAACUGUCAGCUUCUCUCUGACAGUCUCGAACUGUCAAGACAGUCUCAGUUCACAGCCAAGGUGAUCUGUUAACCCUCCCCAUUUCCAGGGCCAAAUCUCAGUUCUUAAGCACGUCGUUUCUUAGCACGGCUUUAUUUUCAUGCUCUUUAUUUCUCUAUUUUGUGCAGCCUUACCCCUUUAAAGUCCACUGUGAGUCCUACCCUGCAGGGCCUCUUAACACAGUAGAGUUCAUGUGCUACUGAUUUGGUGCCUGCCUUCAAACACAUGUGCAAGUUUUGUGGGGUUAAAGAUAGCCACUUGGUGGCACACCACAUUGGAAGUGCUGUUCACCCGGUCAUUUGAAACGGUGUUUGACCACUUGGUGCGCAAAUGGCCUAUCGGAUUAAAGGAUAGCCAAACCCAA